GUUCCACGUGAGCGCCUGCGUUUCUCCUCAAACCUAACGAUGCCGCCGGAGCGGAGGAGACGAAUGAAACUGGACCGGAGAACCGGAGCGAAGCCGAAGCGGAAGCCCGGAAUGAGGCCGGACUGGAAAGCCGGAGCGGGGCCAGGCGGGCCUCCCCAAAAGCCUGCCCCUUCAUCCCAGCGGAAACCGCCGGCCCGGCCGAGCGCGGCGGCCGCUGCGAUUGCAGUCGCGGCGGCGGAGGAAGAGAGACGGCUCCGGCAGCGGAACCGCCUGAGGCUGGAGGAGGACAAACCGGCCGUGGAGCGGUGCUUGGAGGAGCUGGUCUUCGGCGACGUCGAGAACGACGAGGACGCGUUGCUGCGGCGUCUGCGAGGCCCGAGGGUUCAAGAACAUGAAGACUCGGGUGACUCAGAAGUGGAGAAUGAAGCAAAAGGUAAUUUUCCACCUCAAAAGAAGCCAGUUUGGGUGGAUGAAGAAGAUGAAGAUGAGGAAAUGGUUGACAUGAUGAACAAUCGGUUUCGGAAGGAUAUGAUGAAAAAUGCUAGUGAAAGUAAACUUUCGAAAGACAACCUUAAAAAGAGACUUAAAGAAGAAUUCCAACAUGCCAUGGGAGGAGUACCUGCCUGGGCAGAGACUACUAAGCGGAAAACAUCUUCAGAUGAUGAAAGUGAAGAGGAUGAAGAUGAUUUGUUGCAAAGGACUGGGAAUUUCAUAUCCACAUCAACUUCUCUUCCAAGAGGAAUCUUGAAGAUGAAGAACUGCCAGCAUGCGAAUGCUGAACGUCCUACUGUUGCUCGGAUCUCAUCUGUGCAGUUCCAUCCCGGUGCACAGAUUGUGAUGGUUGCUGGAUUAGAUAAUGCUGUAUCACUAUUUCAGGUUGAUGGGAAAACAAAUCCUAAAAUUCAGAGCAUCUAUUUGGAAAGGUUUCCAAUCUUUAAGGCUUGUUUUAGUGCUAAUGGGGAAGAAGUUUUAGCCACGAGUACCCACAGCAAGGUUCUUUAUGUCUAUGACAUGCUGGCUGGAAAGUUAAUUCCUGUGCAUCAAGUGAGAGGUUUGAAAGAGAAGAUAGUGAGGAGCUUUGAAGUCUCCCCAGAUGGGUCCUUCUUGCUCAUAAAUGGCAUUGCUGGAUAUUUGCAUUUGCUAGCAAUGAAGACCAAAGAACUGAUUGGAAGCAUGAAAAUUAAUGGAAGGGUUGCAGCAUCCACAUUCUCUUCAGAUAGUAAGAAAGUAUACGCCUCUUCGGGGGAUGGAGAAGUUUAUGUUUGGGAUGUGAACUCAAGGAAGUGCCUUAACAGAUUUGUUGAUGAAGGCAGUUUAUAUGGAUUAAGCAUUGCCACAUCUAGGAAUGGACAGUAUGUUGCUUGUGGUUCUAAUUGUGGAGUGGUAAAUAUAUACAAUCAAGAUUCUUGUCUCCAAGAAACAAACCCAAAGCCAAUAAAAGCUAUAAUGAACUUGGUUACAGGUGUUACUUCUCUGACCUUCAAUCCUACUACAGAAAUCUUGGCAAUUGCUUCAGAAAAAAUGAAAGAAGCAGUCAGAUUGGCCUGUUGUCUUAACAGAACGGAGGCAAUUCUCGGGUUUUGAAAGUAAGUUGAACUUGAAAAUUAAAUUGUAUAAAAGUAUUGUAAUUUAAAUAGCUAGGUAGUACCUUUGAAUAUACCCUUUGUGUUAGGAAUCCGCAGGACCACCUCCAGGUUUGGUGGCUAACGAGAGAUGACUUCCAGGACUCUGCAUAUGUUCAUUGAACUCAUGGCUAAAAUGUAUUGCAGUGGAAAGGAUACAAAGCAAAAUCAGCAAAGGGAAAGGGUACAUGGAGUAAAGUCCGGAGGAAACCUUCUAAGAGUCCUCUUCUAGUAGAGUCACACAGGACAGUUUAAUUCCUCCAGUAAUGAGUUGUAACAACAUGUGUUAAGUGUUUUCUACCUGGGAAGCUCAUUAGAGACUCAUUGCAGAAGGUUUUUAUUGGGACUUCAUAUAGGGUACCCUCUGCCUAGCAUGUACCAAAAUUCUAGAUUCCCAGAAGAAAAGCCAGGUGUUUAGCAUAAACCACAUUGUUUGUACAAACAGUUUAGGCACAGUGAGCUACCCAUAUCAUUUAGGGAAAGUUUCAUGCCAGUAUAGGAACUGUGUGCUAGUCAAAUUCUCCGACACUAUGCAGUGGCCACCCUUGUAAGCAGACCUUUCUGU